GCUGACAAAAUCAGGAAGUGUGUUGUUAACUUCCUGACUUCUUAUAUUUCAGAGAACGAAGAGUUGAACCAUUUAACAUGAAUUGGGUAAAUAAGAGUGUCCCACAGGAGUUCAUUCUGUUAGUUUUCUCAGAUCAACCAUGGCUAGAGAUUCCACCCUUUGUGAUGUUUCUGUUUUCCUAUAUCUUGACAAUCUUUGGCAAUCUGACAAUAAUUCUUGUGUCACAUGUGGAUUUCAAACUCCACACCCCUAUGUACUUUUUUCUUAGCAAUCUCUCACUCCUGGACCUUUGCUAUACCACAAGUACAGUUCCACAAAUGCUGGUAAACAUAUGCAACACCAGGAAAGUAAUCAGUUAUGGUGGCUGUGUGGCCCAGCUUUUCAUUUUCCUGGCCUUGGGUUCCACAGAAUGUCUUCUCCUGGCCGUCAUGUGCUUUGAUAGGUUUGUAGCUAUUUGUCGGCCUCUCCAUUACUCAAUUAUCAUGCACCAGAGGCUCUGCUUCCAGUUGGCAGCUGCAUCCUGGAUUAGUGGCUUUAGCAAUUCAGUAUUACAGUCCACCUGGACACUUAAGAUGCCACUGUGUGGUCACAAAGAAGUGGAUCACUUCUUCUGUGAAGUCCCUGCUCUGCUCAAGUUGUCCUGUGUUGACACAACAGCAAAUGAGGCUGAACUAUUCUUCAUCAGUGUGCUAUUCCUUCUAAUACCCGUGACACUCAUCCUUAUAUCGUAUGCUUUUAUUGUCCAAGCAGUGUUGAGAAUCCAGUCUGCUGAAGGUCAACGAAAGGCAUUUGGGACAUGUGGCUCCCAUCUAAUUGUGGUGUCACUUUUUUAUGGUACAGCUAUCUCCAUGUACCUGCAACCACCUUCACCCAGCUCCAAAGACCGGGGAAAGAUGGUUUCUCUCUUCUGUGGAAUCAUUGCACCCAUGCUGAAUCCCCUUAUAUAUACACUUAGGAACAAAGAGGUAAAGGAAGCCUUUAAAAGGUUGGUUGCAAAGAGUCUUCUUAAUCAAGAAAUAAGAAAUAUGCAAAUGAUAAGCUUUGCUAAAGACACAGUGCUUACUUACCUUACUAACUUCUCCGCAAGUUGUCCUAUUUUUGUCAUUACUAUAGAAAACUAUUGUAAUCUCCCUCAAAGAAAAUUUCCUUGACAAAAAGCUAUAUUUGUUUCUGUUGCCUAAACAUUUUCAUUGAACAAGCCCCCAGAAUUGG